UUCAAGUUGCCCAUCUCAUUUCACAGGUUAGUGAGAGGGACAAGGAUUCAGGUUCACUGACCCAACCAAAGUGGAGGGGCUAUAUUUGUCCCUGAGUUCCAGAUACAGGUAGUUGGGUGGUCUUAAAUAUAGUCAAGAAUGUUUCCUUCAUGACAAAAAAAAAAAAAAACACUAUACAAUUUUUACUUCUAUAGAACAAACAAUUUUUACUUCUUUUUAAAAGAAGCUCUUUUGAGCUUCUUUUGCUGCAGUAUCUUUUUAUAUGCAUCUAGAUUUUUAUAGAGUCUUGAAAUUCAUUGAUAUAUGAGAAACUGAGGCCACCAAUGACAGAAAUUGUGUAUGUUAGUAAAUUGCGUAUGUUAGUAAAUACGUUAGUAAAUAAGGGUAGCUAAGGAAAACCAAGCCUCUGGGAUUGUAUUGAACAGUUUCAUAGCUGUGGUUCUGUGAGUGAAUGGGAGAGGGCUGGCUUCCUGCAUGUGGGGGUUGGCUGGUGAAUGAGGAAAAUUAGCAUGGCUGGGUUGAUUUUUCUCUUUGAAAAGACUUUGUUCCCAGAUGUCAUACAUAUUAUUUAGCUUGAAUAAAUAUGAAAUAUUCUGGGGAAAUAAAUAUAAGUCCCUGGAGUGCAGAGACUCUCUGUUGCUAACUUCAGUUCAGGUGCUUUCAGUUACAAGAAAGGAGGUGACGUUUGUCUCCAGUGUGUGUGAGUGCUCCCUUGGCUUUUGGCUAAGGUACUUUGCUUCUUUUGCCUUUUAAAAUUCCACUAAUCACUUCAUUUUUCUUUUGGCUCUAGAGAAAGCCAGAGUGUUUUAUUCCUUGAUGAGCAUUUGAGAACUGAAUCCUUUAAUUUAUCUUUUGGUCCACCUUCCAGGACAUGUGUGCACGUGCAUACACACACGCGCACACACACACACACACACACACACACACAAUUUAUCCAUCUCUCUCUUGCUUUUGUGGCAAGCACGUCUUCACCUGUUUUUUUUUUCCCCUUGCAAACUUGAGCAUUGAUUCACAUUUCAAGCCAAUUGUUUAUUGCUGUUGCUAUUGAGAAUGUGACAUUAGGGAGAUUCAGAACAAUGCAUUUCAGCUCACUGUUGACUCAUGUUGGAUGAUUUCAGCAGCAGCAGCUCAAGCUGGUGGCCUGUGGGAUCAAGAUAAUGAGCCUGAAUAGCUGCCGCUGCAGCACUGAGAGGACAAGUAGGGCUGGAGGGACCAACAGCUGGGACCCUUCCAGAAUUCUAAAUGAUCAUGCAAAAGACAGAAACAAGGCAGUUUGCAUCAGGAAAAGGUGAUAAAGGUAGAACAACUUAUUAGAACAGAGAACAAGAUAAAAGGAGUGAUAGGGAAAAGAAUGAAGCCAGAAAAUAUAAUAGUGUAUAACCUUAGGCUAGGAUCCUACUGAAUAAGUCAGCUGGUAAAGUCUAAAAGGAUAAGGUAGUAGAGAUGCUCUGAAGGUUGAAAGUUCUUAUUUUGGUAGAAGGUAGUCAGUUCUUGCUGGCUGUGUUAUAUAAUUAUGUGUCCAUGUUUUGACACAUAUGUUGCUUUCAUCUAUUUUAAAGGUUGUUUUGGAAAAUAUAAGAAAAUUCCCUACAGCAAAUGGCAGGACCCUAAUUAAAAUGAUAAAUGCAAAAGAAUUUAUUGACUCAUCCAGGGGCGAGGCUGACUGGGUUUGGCUGGACUGAAGCAUUCAAAGGAAGAUCUCACUUCCCUGCCUCCCUCCUUCCCUUCCUUUUCUCCUUUUCUCUCCACUUACUCCCCUUUCUGCAUCUCUGCCCCUUCUCCUUCGCCCUGCAUCCUCCCACCAUAAACCUCUCCUCUUCCUCCCUUCUCUCUCGCUUCUUCCUCGCAUCUUUCCCCUGACCCUCCGUCUCUCUGACUCUACCUUCCUCACACCACCCUGGCCCCUCUCUCCAUUGCUUGCUAAUCUCUCUUUCCAUCCCCUUGAUUUCUCUCUCCCUCCACCUCUAGCUGCUACUCUCGCCCCGUCUGCCUCCUCUCCUUCACACCUCAUGCUCCUUUCUCUCUUUGCCCUCGCUUUGUCCCCACUGCUCCCCUGGCCACCCUUGGCCUCCAUUUUCUCUCAUGCUCUGCCUUCCAUUCUUUCUCCUUCCCCCAUUUAUUCUUCCUCACCCCAGCCCUCUCAUGGCUCUGUUGCUCCCUUUGCUAAUUUUGUUCCAGGGCUGACUCUCCUCCGUGGUGACCUGCCUGCUGCUCCAGACUUGUAUCCCCAGCUUGGCCUUCCCAGUGGAAAAAGAGUUUCCCUUUCACAAUAGUUCCAGUAAAAAGUCUCAGGAUUGACUCUCAUUUGGCUGAUGUGGGGACCAAGAGGCUUUAGAACCGAUGGGGGGUGGUGACAUCCCUUUCUGAACCAUGUGGACUGAAGUUCAGGUACAUCAGAGUGCUGGAGAAGGGGAAUUGAGGACUGCAUUCAGAAGAAAGGGGAUUAGAUACCGGGCCGGCAAGAAAACUAAGGCACCAUUACUGUUCCCAUUGGCCAGGCUUGGUUGGUAGUGGCUGUAACAAACAACCCCCACAUCUCAGUAAAAUACAGAAUAAACGGUUUUUUUUUUUCCUUCCCUUUGCCACGGUCCAGUGCAGGUGGGGCCGCCUUCCACAAGCCUUCCUCAGUGUGGUGACUCAGGUGUGGUCCUGCUGUACUGGAGUCCUUCACUUCCAGGGCAUCAAUAGGAGGAAAAGAGUAUAAAACAGGCCGUUAUAGCGACACUCAUGUGGUGUAGAGAAUUCCUGCACACUUCCCAUUAACUGGAACCCAGUUCCUGUUCUUGAUCUUACCAGAAGAGAUACUGGGAAACUUCGUGUUCUUAUGUGCCCAGAAAGAAAGUGAAUGUGGUUUGGGGAGCACACAGCAUUGUUAUGGCCAUAGCCAGGCUGUUUGGAUACAUAAUUGGAUGACAAGCAGCUGGUACUAAACCAAUAUAAAGUUAACGCUGGGUAUUUAUGACUUGUACGUUUAUGCUUUCCUCUGAAAUGCCUUUCAUUCCUUCUUUGAUUUUAGAUAUUGUCCUGAAAUUCUGCUUUUAUGUGAAGCCUUCCAAUAUGGCACUGUAUAAGAGCUUAGACUUUGGAACCAAAUGGCAUAAGUUAAGUUUCAGCUUCCCCAUUUUCUAGGGGGUGACCUGGAGCAAAUUAACCUCAUCAAGCCUUUGUUUCCUCCUCUCAUAUACUGUGCAAAAAGAAUCAUUAAUAAUAAUCCAGAUUUAAAAAGCAUUCAAAUCACUUGGGUGCUUGUGACGUUUUCUUUUUUUAGCUGUAAUUUUACUUAGCAACUCAGUGAAGCUCAGCAAAUCAGUGGUACAUCUGGGCGUGGGCUGCACUGUAGGCUCCCAUUUUCCAUCCACUAGAAUCUUAUGAUUUCAGAGCCAAAGGGAAGUUCAGUGGUCACCAUUCCAACCUCCCCAUUUUACAGAAGAGGAAACUGAGGCUCAGGCAACUUGAUUGUGCACAUGGUGGCAGAGCUGGAGGUAGGUCCCAUGUCCCCCGAUUCUGCAUCUUCUGAUUCCGCAUCUGAGAGCCUGUGGCUCCUCUCUCAGCGGUGGCCUUUUUCUUUUGCAAAUCUUGUUACCUCAACACAUCAAAACCUGGCAGUCUAAGGAGAAGGCUCCUCAGUUCUACCCCACAGCUCAGGAAAAAAAGGCCUGGCUGGCAUGGUGGCUCAUGCCUGUAAUCCCAGCACUUUGGGAGGCCAAGGCGGGCAGAUUACCUGAGGUCAGGAGUUCGAGACCAGCCUGACCAACAUGGUAAAACCCCAUCUCUACUAAAAAUACAAAAAAUUAGCCGGGCAUUGUGGCAGGUGCCUGUAAUCCCAGCUACUCAGGAGGCCAUGGAAGGAGAAUCGCUUGAGCCCGGGAGGCUGAGGUUGCAGUGAGCAGAGAUUGCGCCAUUGCACUCCGGCCUGGGCAACAAGAACGAAACUCUGUCUCGAAAUUAAAAAAAAAAAAAAAAGCCUGUUCAUUAGGUUCUCGGUUCUCUCUCCGUACCCACCCCCUGCCCCCCAAAUCAAGUGUAGACAUCUUUUUUGUGUUCUAGACAUAAGACCGUCCUAUCUGCAGCAACUGUGGUUUAAAACUUUUUGGUUUUACAGAGAUGGCUGCUGCAGCUCAAUGAGAGGUGAUAAAGACAUAGGUAAUUGCUGUAGAAUAAUCCUGCUGCCAAGAAGAUGAUUGAACUCCCACACAGAAGUCACUCCUGAAGCCAUUGGCUUCUUGUCUGCUGUUGGGGUCUUUAUUGUUCUUCUGGCCGUCCUCUUCCUCUUCAUCAACAAGAAGCUGUGUUUUGAAACGAUAGGAGGCCUUCCUUUCCUGGAGCAUCGAGGGAAAAGAAAGCAUUCUAAAGACAAGACUGGGAUUCACAAGGGGCUGGUCAACAGCUUUGGGGAUGACGAAGAGCUGUCCACAUCUUCUGACAGUGACGAGGAGGUGAUCAAACAAUUUGAGAUUUCCGUGUCCCGGUCCCAGAGUUUCCGUUCAGUGACAUCUGAGAAAGGAAAGCAGACAGGAUUGGAGCAGAAACCAAAAUUCAGCCGUUCGUUGUUGACACACGGAGAAGAUGGCACAGAAGUAUCUGCCUGCGAAGAUUUGGAUGGAGCCAGCCAACGGCGUUAUUCUGAGAAUCUCUCCUACGGUGAAGAUGACCACAUCCCUGCUCACUCACAGUCCCCAUGUGAAAGAGGGGAUGCCAAACACCACGGCACAUCUCACCAAGAGUCCAGUGUGGUCCAAAGCCUCAGGCGCCAAUCCACAGAGGGCAGCUUGGAGAUGGAGACAGCUUUUAAUAGCCGGGGAUUUGAAGAUUCCUAUGCCACUGACAGCUCCUCCAUGUGGAGUCCAGAGGAACAGGACAGGACCAAUUUGCAGGUGCCAUCCGGGGUCUCAGAGCCCAUCUCAAAGUGUGGUGACCUAGAUGUCAUCUUUGAAUAUAGAGCCGCCAGCCAGAAGCUCACAGUGACCAUUGUGAGGGCACAGGGCCUCCCAGAUAAGGACCGAAGUGGUGUCAACUCCUGGCAAGUUCAUGUAGUGCUGCUGCCUGGUAAGAAACACAGGGGCAGGACGAACAUACAGAGAGGGCCCAACCCCGUCUUCAGGGAGAAGGUCACCUUUGCCAAGCUGGAGCCCAGAGAUGUGGCUGCCUGUGCUGUCCGCUUCCGCCUGUACGCUGCCCGGAAGAUGACCCGAGAGAGAAUGAUGGGAGAGAAACUAUUCUAUCUCAGCCACCUGCACCCAGAAGGGGAAAUGAAAGUGACUCUGGUUCUGGAGCCAAGAAGUAAUAUAAGCAGUGGAGGGUCUCCGCUCAGCCCAUCUGCGGUUUCUCACAGUGAUAGUACUUCAUCCACGCAGUCGCUGUCUCAUGGAGGGGCGCCAGAGCUGUUGGUGGGGCUCUCGUACAAUGCCACAACGGGGCGAUUAUCUGUGGAAAUGAUCAAAGGCAGCCAUUUCCGAAACCUCGCUGUUAACCGAGCACCUGAUACAUAUGGAAAACUCUUUCUCCUCAAUUCUGUGGGUCAAGAGAUGUCCCGUUGCAAGACGUCCAUUCGGCGUGGUCAGCCCAAUCCUGUCUAUAAGGAGACCUUUGUUUUCCAGGUGGCCCUCUUUCAGCUGUCUGAUGUCACGUUGAUGAUUUCCGUUUAUAACAGGCGUACUAUGAAGCGUAAAGAGAUGAUUGGCUGGAUUGCCCUGGGCCAGAACAGCAGUGGAGAGGAGGAACAAGAUCACUGGGAGGAGAUGAAGGAAACCAAAGGCCAGCAGAUCUGCAGAUGGCACACUUUGCUGGAAUCCUAGGUUUGCUAACCUGCAUUUGUGUGCUGUGUCCACCUUGGUUACCUGUGUUGCUGUCUACUGACACUAAGUGUCCUGGCAAGGGUUUCAGGGUUUCAAAAACAGAUUCCACUAACCCCUAGGACAUUGUGAGUGGGAGUUUUGGGUUUCUCAAUGGUCUGAUUUGGAUUUAAAUAUUGUAAUUUUAAAAACACACAUACACAGUGAAGUGUCCGUAUGGAAAAUAUUAUACCACAAUUAAGACCACUGAUGAGUUAAUUUGUGCCAAUAGAUCAUUGAGUUUUAGUUCAGGGUAUGGGGUGAAGCUUCUUCUGCUGUCUCUGUUUGCUUGAAGAGUAACCUGAGAUUGCAAGGGAGCUGUUAAUUGUUACUAUUUGCAACCAUUUAGGUGGAUGAAUCAGAAUUUUCUUAAUAUGGUACAAAAAACUCCAAAAUAUAGAUAUGAAUCAGAUGCUGAGCCUCAUAAAAGAAUCAAACUCUAAUCCAUAAACUCUUAUUUCACAUUUUUCUCUUUAUCAAAGAAACCUAUUUACCUAACGAGUAAAUAUUAUAAACUUGCACUUUUAAAAUAAAUUUGUAUUAAUUAAAUACCUCUUUUAUCUUAUAUUUUGUGGUUUCUAUGAGAUUUGGUUAGAUGAAUCAUUUUGAAGCAAGAAAAGAGUUCAGAAACUACUGUUUUAAGACAACUUGUCUCCUUUUGAAUAUGUAAGAUUUCAAACUUGUGACUUUCAAGGUUUUUAUGCUGUCUUUCUCACCCAAUAAGUUCUUACAGAAUAAGAAAACAAAAAACAAGACUACUGCAGUCAUAGAUUUAUUGAUUUUUUCUGCUUCUGGUGUUCUUUUGGAUUAUCCUUUUUCUAUGUUCAAUUAUAUAUACUCAUAUAUGAAUAUUUUGAAUGUACUGCAUGUAAACCAUGCUCUUUUUAAACUGAGUAUUUUCCAUCACUAGAGCAUAGUAAAUUGUACACAGUGAGUCCUUAAUAAAUAUUGAUUUGAUUGACUCUUCAAAGUGAACAUGUUAUAACACCUGUGAAUGGAGAAAUAUUUUCAGCUUGUGUGGAAUGACAUUAAGUUUUUCUUUGAGCAUUUGAAGUGCCUAUAACUGUCAUUUUUUUAUGGCAUUUGCAGCAACAUAUAUUAGUCACUACUUGCAAUCUGGGCAUGUGCCAUUCAGAAUACUGAUCUUGUAUGGUUAUGAGCAUGGGAUUUUACUUAUGACUUAAUUUUACAUAUUUAUGCAGUGCAUGUUUACUUUCCUUAUUCAUAGGUCUGGGCCCUUAAUUUCAAUUACUUUAAAUUGGCAUUAAUAAAAAAAUAGGGAAAGAAUGUAUGUACAUUUAAUCCCUGCGCUCAAUGUGCAGCUCUUCUGAGCAAUUGCUCAGUCACCUAUUUUUAGUUUCUAUGUUUCAUUGUGGACUUUUUCCUGUCUGUGGGAAGAGUGAUAGCUAGUGAUGGCUGUAUACAGUUAAAAACACAUAACUCCUCCUCAGCUCCACGUUUUGACAGAUUGUAAGCGUAGGCUGUAACACUUGAAGAACAUAUUUAUUCCUUACAGUGUGUAAUGGUUAUCCUGACAAGACCAGACUAGGGCACAGGAUAACUCUACUAUGCUUUCAGGGUUCAGUCUUUGAAUGAAAUGAUUUCAUAUGGAAGAAUGAGAAUUUGCCAAAUAAAUUAAUACCUUAAUUACUUUUCAGGUCAUGGGAGUUUCAUAUAUAUGGCUGCUCAGUUAUUAGGAAUAUGUAAUAAAACCAUGUUCCUCUGGGUUUUUACCCUACCUUUCUUUGGGAGAUCUCAGAGUGCUUUUCCAGCAUUAUAUCCAUUAACUGCUGAGUGGUCUUUGCAGCGUGGCUAAGUCAUUGAGUAGAACUGAGUGCGAUUGAUUAAGUAGCAGCACAAAGAAGUGGCUUUUCACAUCUCUUACUCUUUAUGCCUUGUGUUUAAAGGGAAGUAGAACAGCCUCGCUAUGCUUUCCUUUAUGCAGUAACAUAAUAGCAGCAUUCAUUUUAAAAUUUACAUUUGAAAAAAAUCUGUAUAUAUUGUACAGACAGCCCUGAAUUUUUCCCUCUCAUAUUUUCCUGCUGCUGCAUCCUUGUUUCUUGGUACCCAAUAAUCACCUAUACUUCAUUUUCUGUUCCCAAGACCCACCCAUUUUUAAGGUUUUCGGCUGGUGUAGUGAAGAUAUUUGUGUGCUUGAUCUGCCUUCCAAUGGUCUGUUUAUGAUACAGUUUACAGGAAUGCGCACCAUUUUAAGGGAAGGAAUGCCUGAAAACAUUUUUUAUUUUUAUAAUUUUACUAUGUUGGUGCUACUCACCAAAUAGGAUGCAUGUACAUCUUGAAUAUACAGCAACAUUCACCCUCAGCUGAUUGUAUACAUUUAAGUGCUGAAGACAAGAUAUAUAACAAUAUGUGGCUGAUUUUUUUUACCUUUAUUUGAAAUUCUAGUUUAGUAAGAUCUUUUGAUUUUGUGCACUUAAACUCCCUUAUUUUCUUGGCAAAGUCUAGACACAAAUGCAUUUAACAUGUUUUUCACUUGAGCUUUUACAUUUGGUUUUCAAAAGAGUUAUGAAAGAUAAUUAGUUGGUUCUGCAGUAAAAAACUGCUUUUGCCUAUUUCUUCCAGCUAAUGAUUAAUAUCUCAUAGGGAGAUUUGACAUUGAAGCAGCACUGGUUUUUGUUGCUUGAGUAGGUCUUUCAGCGAUUUUGCCUGAAGAGCAUGCUUUUAAAAUAAUAUCGUUAAGAGUAAAUGAUGCGCUGGGUUUAUGGAAAUCUGCUUUAUAGUGUGCCUUCUUUUAGGGUGUGAGUUUACACUGAAUUGAGAAAUCCUGAUUUCACCAAUUACGGUGGUGGCUGUUGUACUCUCUACUCCCCUCUGACUAUUGUUGAAUUUUUAAAUGGACCAUUCACCAGGCAGCCGAACACCUGCUCUCCGUUCCCUCUCCUUCACUGGCUCCCAGUGUGAUGCACAGUUGUUUUGGACUCUGUUUUUGCUGAUGCUGCAUAACUGUUGGAGGUGGGGGUGUCUUGCCUUCCCUAACAUAAGAAGAAUUUGUAAUGUCUUUGGAUGUGGCAUUCCACCUGCAUGAAAUCAGGAAAAGAAUCAUCACCAUGUUUGUGAGAGGGAAAAGAGUAUGGCAUUGCAUAGUCAUUCGCUUUAGGCACUAUUAAUUCUGACAUCCUUCAUUGAAAAUUAACUGACAUCAAAUGUCAAUAUUCUCCAUAGUCCUAGGUGCCAGUGAGCCUGAAACACAGCUUCUGCCUUUUCAAUGUGUAGAUUUCAUGAUAUUUUACAAAUUAUUGUUACCUCUUGUGCAGUUACUGUGCUUUAGAUGACCUUAUCUGAGAACCAAAAUUCUUUUCUUUCCAGAUGAAGUACUAUUUAAGUAGAAACUAGCAUUAGGUUAAAUCAAAGUGCUUCUCUGAUAGCCACCAAUUUGAUUUAAUUGAUGAUUCGGUGUGGACACCACUGUGGGUUUCCAAAAAAACUGGUUAUCCUUUUGCAGCAGAGGACUUAGUAUUUUAAAAACAGAAAAGUAAGUAGGAAAGUAUUAUUUGUAAAUGUCAUAAAACCAGAUGGAGGCAUAUUCUUUACUGAUAAAGAAACAGGACUAGAACACGCAUGUGGUAUCUCCUUUUACUUUUGAGGAAACUGUGGUUAAAGAACAUUCUAUUCUAUUUGAUCUAAGAGCAAAGCAAAUGAUGGAUAAUCCUGAAAUGGUAAAAGUAUUUUUGUCUUAAAAAUUAUUCAUUUGGGCAAAGUCAUUUACAACAAAAUAAAAAGUCAUACAGCACACCUAUGGAAGAAUUAAAGAAUACAUAAAUGUGCUGGAUACAUUUAGCAUCCUCCAGUGAGUUGUAUGUAAGGAGAGUAAACUAAUAAACCAAAAUACAUAUCAGAUCAACUAGCUAUCACUUUUCUAAAACUUGUAGAAUUCUGAAAAAUAUUUAAAGAUGGGAGAAACGAAACUGUGCUAAGACAAUGAGAUUGGCAUAGCACAGUGAAGUUGGCACAAACUGUGAUCCUGGCCUGGGUUUACAUGAAACUCUGCUGUGUGGCCUUAAGAAAAUUACUUAGCCAGCCUGUAUCCUGGUUUCUUCAACUGGAAAAUGGAAAUAAUACCUACCUCAUUAGGUGUCUUAAAAGAUAUCAGUGAAAUCACAGAUGUAAUGUGCCUAGCAUAGAGCCGGGCAUGUAGUUAGCAUUCCGUAGUUCCUCCUUACAGUCAUGCCUGAAAAAGAAAAUAUUUAAGAUGUGUCUUCUUUUUCUAGCAAAUGUUAUUAUAACACUAGAGAAAAACAAAAACCAACGUUCAGAUACUGUAACAAGGAUAGGCUCAUGAAGCCAGGCUGGAUUCGUAAAUAAAGGAGGCUUCAUCAGGACAGCCUAAUCAGAGAUAAGCCUGGUAUGUGGAGGAAAUUGAGCCUUAAUAGAGUCCAACUGUGGUAGAACCAAGUCUUUGCAUUUAUCCCCUUAGUUUGGAGGGAGUACAAAUCCUUGAUGGUUUGUGUGUACCUCUUGAUCGAUCACAAACAAGGCCUCUCCUUGUCUCCAGUUCUCUUAUUCAUAAAUGGACAAGGCAUCUUGUCGCCUUUAUCAAAAGAGUUGGUGACAAUGGCAGUUUGACUACAUAUUUCAACUGUGAUCCAAAAAAGUAAAAUAAAUGAUGUGAUACUAUACUGAGACUGUUUUAAAAAUGGAUAACACUUUCUUUAAAACCUGCAUUAUAUAUCCAUUUUAUAUCCUGAUAGCCAAACAUUUUAAAAUACUCUAAUAACACAGCUCUCAAAACGUAUCUGUUUGACUGGAAUGUCCUGCUCAGAACAAAUUAUCACUGUUUCCCUUAUGAGAUCCUAAUGAAAGAAAUUCAGUUGAUACUACUUUUUAAAAUGGGUUUUAAGAGUGGCUUGUUGAUAUAAUAGCGCAUCCACUUGUUCUCAAGUGAUUCAAACCUUGAGUAAAAAGGAGAGUUUCUGGAGAAUUUAGAAGAAUCUUUGUUGACAUUUAAUCUAGAGAAGUCUUCAGGAGCAAACCACUUCAAGUUCAGUGUAACCAGGUGCCAUGAGUCAGUCAUGUGCUACUUGUGGUUUUAAACGAAACAUGAUUCUGGGAUGAGAAGUGCGAGGCUACACUCCUAAUAUAAUCAAAUUGCCAAAGCACUGUUUUGAGUCCUCGGUAUCCCAAUUAAGGAGAAACAUGAAGACAUUGGAGAAUCACUUAGCUUAGGGCUUUUAGUAGGGAAUAAUUAAACAUGUAGGGAAGGUGAAGGAGUUAGAUGGGAGGUAAGAAGGCUGAGGAGAUUUCUAGUAACAAUGAUCCAAAAGUUCUAACCAGGGGGAUGGUGCACACUUUCUCUUCUUGACCACAUGGAUAGAUUUCAGAGCAUCCCUCUAAAUCAAGUCUGGAGAAUUAUGUGAAGGUUGUUUCUCAUUAAUUCAAAAUGUAUUCAUUGUCUAGUACUAUGCUAUCUGGGCUGGCACAGAACUUAAAAUCUCUUUGGAGUGCUAUGAGUGCACAUUGAAGCAGUUGGUCAUCAUUAUACAAUGAUGCUUACCAAUAUACAACUGUUAAGUUAGUCUAACUAUGUGCCAUAAACAGUAGAGUUCCUUGUUACUAGUAUUGGAAGGUGAAACAUUGGCUGAAUUUAUUGGGGCAAGUGUCUAGGAAGCCUUGGACUGGCAGUGAGUCUUGGUUGCAUUAUAUGGGAAAUUGGUGGGGAUGGGGGUGUCAUAGAAUCAUCAUCUUUGGAAGUUUUUUAAAAUAGAAAAAUGUACUUGAAGUCUUGGUUCUGCUAAAGAAGAAUGAGAGGACACCCAUGAAUAUACCCUUUAUAAAGUUCCUUCUAAUAUUUAGGUGUAACGUUAAAAAAGAAUCAACAAUAACACUCCAGGCCUGUCUUCUUCCACUUUGGACAUUUUUUCCACAUUGAUUUUUCUCUGCAUCAUAGAAAGUUUUCUCUGAAGAGUUCCUAUUUGGGUUUUGUUUAGGGCUUUGGGGAUGCCUGCAGGCUCAGGGGGAGUUUCCUCUCCUAUGGUGCUUUGACUGUUUUUGUUUCCCUUGGGUCACAAAACCAUAUCCUAGACACACAGACAAUAAUCACCUUAUUUAUAUCCACUGUGGAACCUGUGAAACAGCUCGAGGCUUUACAGAACAAGCUCAUAGGCAGUCAUGGAGAUCUGAGGCCUUUCUUGGAAUGAAGCCGCUAACUUGCUAACUGCUUUCCAUUGCUCACUAAUGCUGCCUUAAGGUUUCUUCAUGGGAAUUUUUACUUCAUGCCUUUGAGUGACAGUGUUACCAGUUUUACCUUGAGGAUGAUGAGAAGGCUGACUUCCUAUUGUAUUGCCAUAUUUAUGCAUUAUUUUUGUUUACGUCAUUUCCCCCUUGAAGUAUCUAGUUGCUGGGGUUUUGUUUGUUUUAUACAAAAUUUAUUCAUUCAAAAAGAUCUUUAUAGGUUGGGCAUGGUGGCUCACACCUGUAAUCCCAGAACUUUGGGAGGCCGAGGUGGGAGAACAGCUUGCGUCCAGGAUUUCUAGUCCAGCCUGGGCAACAUAGUGAGAUCUUGUCUCUACAAAAUACCAAACAUUCGCUGGGUAUGGUGGUGUGCGCCUAUAGUCCCAGCUCCUCAGGAAGCUGAGGUGGGAGGAUUGCUUGAACCUGUGAGGUCAAGGCUGCAGUGAGCCGGGAUCAUGCCACUGCAUUCAGCCUGGGUAGCAGAGUGAGACUCUGUCUCAAAAAAACCAAAAAACAAGACCUUUUUAAGUGUAAAUGUUCCAGACUCAGGGUUAGGGGUUGGAGAAUGGCAGAUGGAUAAAAUAGUUUAAGUUCAACAAUAUUUUUUUGUUGUUUCUAAAUAUUCUUUUUAAAAACUAGAGUCUGAUAAGAAAUCUAGGUAAAUAAUAAGAUCUUUUAUUAACCUUGAAUUUUUGGCUUAAUGUAUUUCUGUAAUUGUCUCUUUCCCCCUUUGAAAGGCAGAAGAUUUAGGGAAGGUGAAAGUUAUUACCCUGUAUCUAAUUAAGAAAUAGGUACACUUGUUUGUCAGUCUAUGCUUUCAUUCAAAAUAAAUGGAUAUGUUUUGUAUCUGGGGGAGGAAAUGCAUCAUUCCAUUCCAGCAGUGAAAAGAAUUAUAGCAUCAAAUAGGAUAUUUAGUAUUCUUGACUUUUAUAAUUAAAUACUGAAUGCCCUUUGCAAGACAGUAAGUUAGAUCCUGGAAUGCUAGGUCUGUACAAACUUGACACAUUUCUUACAAGCUCUGUGUUUUAAUAGUCAAAGGCAUUGCUACCCUUUGCUUUUUGAAAGAGUGAACUGGUAACAGUAGCCGCCAGAGAAAGAGGUGACAAUCUAAACAAAGAGCCCUGCUUACCUUUCUGUGACUAAAACUAGUCUUAAAAACUGAAUACAUUUGGGGCAUCCUUAUGAAAUAGGUAAAGGUCAACAUUGGGAGUGUCCCUACCUUGGCAGAUAGACCAAUACUUUUUUCCUAGACUCAACCCAUUUUUAAAGCAGGAGUUUUUCCAAUGGAUUUAUUGUUUAUAAUUCUACUAAACAUGUCUUAGUCCACGCAAAUUAACUCAAAAUCUUUGGUGGCCUGAAAAUUCUGACUGAAAGCAAGUUUUUCGUGUUGCCCAGUUGAUAGUCCAUAAUAAAAAAUGUACAUAUCUUGUUUAAAAAAGACCUUGAUGUUUGAGAAGAAAUAUCGGAAGUCUGCCAGUAAAAACUCUGAUUAAGUGAGGAACAUGUACAUUAAAAGAUAUUUUCAUGUAAGUUAUUUUAAGAUAGUUGCAUUCUAGGACCAUGUUUCUUUUUUGAGAGUGUUUCUUUGUCAAGUUCCUUAUAGCCAAUGCCUUGACCAAAGCUUACUAAUUUUGCCACAUUUCCUUGUGGGUUAUGAUAAUCUUUAUUAAUUCACAACUCUACCAAAUUAUAAUACAGUCUUUUAUUAUGCCACCAUAUGAAUGCAGCUGCAAAUUCAAUUUUGUGAAAUACAAAGUCCUUUCCAGAAUUUUAAAACUUAAUUUCAGUAUAGAUUUUAAGUUUGUGAAUAAGAAAUUAGUAUUUGUAUACCUUAUUAUGACAGAGGUUUCUGUUACAAUAUUUUCUCUUAUAGUGUUGGGAUAGGAUUUGACCUGUAUUUUCAGGUUAAAGCUGGUCUUUGAGAUCUACUUUUUAAGAAAUUAAUAAAUUUUAUUUUUUAGAGUUUUAGGUUCACAGCAAAAUUGAUCCUAAAAUAUAGAGUUCUCAUAUACUCCAAACACAACCUUCUUCCCCGUGAACAUUUUGAACACCACAGUGCUAUAUUUGUUACAACUGAUGAACCUUCAUUGACAUAACAUUAUCACCCAAAGUGCAUAGUUCAUAUUAAGGUUCACUCUUGGUGUUGUGUAUUUUAUGGGUUUUGACCAAUGCACAAUGACGUGUGUCCACUAUUGUAGUAUCAUACAGAAGAUUUUCACUGCCCUAAAAAUCCUCUGUGCUCUGCCUAUUCAUUCCUCCCUCCCACCUAAGCCCUGGCAUCCACUGGUCCUUGUACUGUCCCCAGAGUUUUGCCUUUUCCAGAAUGUCAUACAGUAUGUAGCCUUUUCAGAUUGGCUUUUUUUUUUUUCACUUAGGGAUAGUCAUGUAAGUUUUCAUGUCUUUUUAUGGCUUGAUAGUUCAUUUAUUUUAAGUGCUGAAUAAUAUUUCAUUGUCUGGUUGUAUCACCAUUUAUGACCUAUUUGCUCUUAUUUCUAGUUCCAGUUGCUAUGGCAAAUUUUAUUAAAGUGCGUGCUCUCAGGAAAAGCUGCAUAUAUUUUAUAUGAUCCAUCAAAUAAAAUGUAGCAACUUCCAGUCUAGAAUAAAUUUCACCUAUAUGAUAUUGAGCUUGUUUUACAUUGGGGGAGGAGAUUUAUGAAAAAAUAUAAUAAUUUCAUAAUUUAUAUUACCCUAUCUAUGAGUUUUUCCCUCCAUUGGAAUCUAAACAGAAAGUUCUGAAGGUUAUGAAGACGUGAUCCCAAAUUUAGUGACUCUGUAGUGUCUUUUGUUGAGCAAUGAGUUAAAUACCUGUCGAUAAAAAGUGUUAAUUAUGUUAUUACUGAUUCAUGAUAGAAAAUCACCUUCUGUCGCUAGUUUAUAUGACUUUACAUUUACCACUCCUGCCAAGAGAAAGGAAGCUUUGUGAUUGUGCCCCGUCAUAGUUAAUUGUACAAAUCAAUUAAAAAUGGUAUGUAAGCAUCUGGCUCACACAGCAGCUCUGAAUUCUGAAUGAAAAGAUAACCCAUGCUAAUGUAUAUGUUGCAUGAACAAGUAGAUGGGUGUUGGAAAGAAAACACUGAUAGUCACUCUGGGUGAAGGGGGAGGCCUGGCCAAUGAUUUGUAUCUGAGAAACAUUUUGAGAUUAUUUAUAUGUCUUCUGACUGCCCUUUGCUUUGUAGCUACAGCAACUUGCAGAACCUGGCAUUAUUGCAGAGAUGAAGGUAUAGUUGUAUAAAGAAUAUUGGAUUAAAGUUGAUGAGGCCUGUGUUCUGAUAUCAAAUCUUCCACUAAUGAGCUCUAAAAUGAAUAUCAAGUCACAAUUUUUUCAAGCCUUCAUUGUUGCAUCUAUCAGAUGGGAAUAGUAAUACUCAUUUUACCUAUUUUUACCAGGUGGUUGUAGGAACAGGAUUCAUUCAUUCCUUCAUUAAUAUAAUGAACACUUUGAGACCCCACUAUAUAACAGGGCCAUACAUAUGACAAGGUGAUAGAUGGAAAGACGUUUUGCAGAAUUUUUGAAGACUUGCAAUGUUUUUGAAGACUACAGGAUAGUUUGUGAUUUUUAUAUUAAGGUCGUAUCAACUCUUUAUGUCAAUAUAUCAAAGUAAUUGACACUUUUAGAGCUCUGCCAAUCAGUGGGCCAUAUUCAUAGAAUGUCAGUAAUCUGUCUGAAUACAAGUUAUAGUUGGUCUUUAGCUGUUCUGUCUCUGAGGAGCUAGAAAUAAAAUAUUAGGUUCUAAUUUUUUUUUGUUCAAACACUGAUCAUGUAACAAACUGCAAAUCCAUGUUUUCAGCAGGUUCGCCAACCUUUGAGUUGAAUGCAGACCUUUCUUUAGAACAACCUAACUUUGAGUACAGGCAAAGUAUUAAAUGGAAUAGCUUUUCCUCCCCUACAAAGUGGAUUUGAAUACAGUCCUUAGAAAAAUUCUUCCCCUGCCAAAAAAGGUCCUUCAAUCUCCUUUAUUAUUUUUCUUUUGAAGAAUCAAACUUGUCCAUCUCUCCCCUCCCAAGUGACUUUCCUCACUCAUGUAAUCAUUUUCUUCAUAAAUGCCCUUUUACUAUCCCACAGAAAAAGUAAAGAUUUAAAAAAUCAUUUUUAAGGUACAUCCAAGAUUUCAUAGCAAUAUUUUAUUUGUGUUCACAGUGCAAGAUAAAUCUGACUUUCUCAAUAUUUUUGGUCUUCAUAUGGCAUCUGAAACAGUUGUUCACAUUCACACAUUUAUGUUUCACCAUAUGCAUACUGUGUACAGCUCUGUUGUUCUAAAAUAUUUUAUUGGUUUUCCUUUAUAUCUCAACUUUUGAUGGGUGUCCUUGAAGAACUUUCAUGAAAAAAAUGUAAAUGUGAAUGAUUCAUUCAUUUUGAACAUAUGUAACUAUUUUAGGAGAUUUUCAGGAGAUUUUACCCUACAUGGAGUACACUGUUCUUAGCAGGGAAUGUGCUUUAUAUUACUAUUCUACUCACAGCUGGAUGCUGCAGAUGUAUUAACAUUGUAAACAUGUACUUUUUCUAUUCUAUGCUUACUUUAAUACAUUAUUUAUAUGUGCUAGACUGUGCUGAGUUUUGGUGGUUGUCAAAGGCAGUCAGUAAUUUUAUAAAUUUCACUUUUGUGGAUAGUUAAGUAUAACAUGGUUUAGUAUAAAAUCUGGUCUUCCUCUAGAUUUCUAAGUCACUAGAAGAAUUUCUUGGCAAAUUGAUUGUUCAAGGCCAGUUUUGUUAGUUGUAAGGUGGAAGCCACCCCAAUCCUCUCCCAGUGUUUCAUAGGCAUUUUCAGACCUGGAUGCUAUUAUAGUUCCUCCUCUAGUUUUCCAGUAGAGAAUUCGUAUGUGGUCCAGAGGUUCAAGAGAGAGAGAGAAAAAAUUUCUCCUCAAAAGAAUUGAACCCUUACUUUAGAAACUUCUGACAAUCUUCAGAACAUUCCAUGUGGGUGUCCUUGUGUUUCUCAUAGUAUGACUUAUUGAUUCAUGGUGUCUCUUAUUAAAGAAGCAUGAAUGUAUCACUAGCUGUUACCAGAACAAACAGCUGUAGAAUGUAAUGACCCAUCCUAUUUCUAAAUUUACUUCUAUCAGUGGAUAAUUUGUGUAUAGGAAAAGGUGUGGAAAUUUUUUAAUUGUUAAAAACUGGAAUACCUUUCUACCUUUUGUAGUCUUUAAGAUUUCAUAAUGAUGGUUUUAAUGUAUUACUAUCUUACUAUUAUGUAUUGUGUUUAAACAAGACCAAUCAGUGAAAUAUUGAAUGUCAAUACUUUUUGUUAGAAAUGCCCUCUGAAAAUGUUAGAAAAUGUAAAACUUUACCUGUGACAAGGAAUAAAUUCAUGAUUAGAAGAAUUAUACUGUUUUUCUUGUGCAAAUAAUACUUAAGGCAGAUGUUCAGUCUCACAGUGAUGUUGGAAAGCAUAUUUUAUGCAGUCUAAACACUAUUUCUGUAUUAGAUAUUUAAAUGCAUGAGGAUAAAUUCUAAUUGCUUUUUGUUUAAAACAGAAACAUAGAAGAAGCAUUAGCCCCAGUUUGUAUAAAAUGUCUGCUGCAACUGAAUUCAUGAUAGUUCAUGAAAACUGAAAAUCAUUCCAAUUUUGUAAAACUGCUGCUACUGGUUUUAUCAAUAAAGUUUUAGCAGAUGGCUUAUA